ACACACAGCCCCCGCCCCAACACAUACACACACGGCUUCUUUCUGUCUGGGAGUCCCUGGACAAGUCACAUGGGAUUCUGCGCUGGGAGGAACAGGGUAAGGCGUGAACGUGGAGGGCAGUUUCCCUUUCAGGUCCCGGCUCUCUUGGCUUUCCCAUAAGCAGCUGCCUUGGGACUCUCCUGGAGACCUGAUGCCCACAGCCAAGCUGACCACAGGAGCCGGUGCUGGGGACUGAGGGAAACUUAGAGUUCAGAGAGGGGGUGUGAUUUGCCUGAGGUCACACAGCAAGUUAGAGACCCAGCUCCACGACUCAUUGUCUUGGCUUUGGCCCUCGUCAUCCUGCCCACCCAGCGGGGCUUCCCAACCCACCACACAGCCAUGGACGGGAAGGUGGCAGUGCAAGAGUGUGGGCCUCCUGCAGUCUCCUGGGUCCCCGAGGAGGGAGAGAAGUUGGACCAGGAAGACGAGGACCAGGUGAAGGAUCGGGGCCAAUGGACCAACAAGAUGGAGUUUGUGCUGUCAGUGGCCGGGGAGAUCAUUGGGCUGGGCAAUGUCUGGAGGUUUCCCUAUCUCUGCUACAAAAACGGAGGUGGAGCCUUCUUCAUCCCCUACUUCAUCUUCUUCUUUGUCUGCGGCAUCCCGGUGUUCUUCCUGGAGGUGGCGUUGGGCCAAUACACCAGCCAAGGGAGUGUCACAGCCUGGAGGAAGAUCUGCCCCCUCUUCCAGGGCAUUGGUCUGGCAUCUGUGGUCAUCGAGUCAUAUUUGAAUGUCUACUACAUCAUCAUCCUUGCCUGGGCUCUCUUCUACCUGUUCAGCUCCUUCACUUCUGAGCUGCCCUGGACGACCUGCAACAACUUUUGGAACACAGAGCAUUGCACGGACUUUCUGAACCACUCAGGAGCCGGCACAGUGACCCCAUUUGAGAAUUUUACCUCACCUGUCAUGGAAUUCUGGGAGAGACGAGUUCUGGGCAUCACCUCGGGCAUCCAUGACCUGGGCUCCCUGCGCUGGGAGCUGGCCCUGUGCCUCCUGCUCGCCUGGGUCAUCUGCUAUUUCUGCAUCUGGAAGGGGGUCAAGUCCACAGGCAAGGUGGUUUAUUUCACAGCCACGUUUCCGUACCUGAUGCUUGUCAUUUUGCUGAUCAGAGGUGUCACCCUUCCCGGAGCCUACCAGGGCAUCAUCUACUACUUGAAGCCAGAUUUGUUCCGCCUCAAGGACCCUCAGGUGUGGAUGGAUGCGGGCACCCAGAUCUUCUUCUCCUUUGCCAUCUGCCAGGGGUGCCUGACAGCCCUGGGCAGCUACAACAAGUAUCACAACAACUGCUACAAGGACUGCAUCGCCCUCUGCUUCCUGAACAGUGCCACCAGCUUUGUGGCUGGGUUUGUUGUCUUCUCCAUCCUGGGCUUCAUGUCCCAAGAGCAAGGGGUGCCCAUUUCUGAAGUGGCCGAGUCAGGUCCUGGGCUGGCCUUCAUCGCCUUCCCCAAGGCUGUGACUAUGAUGCCCUUAUCCCAGCUGUGGUCCUGCCUGUUCUUUAUCAUGCUCAUAUUCCUAGGGCUGGACAGCCAGUUUGUCUGUGUGGAGUGCCUGGUGACAGCCUCCAUAGACAUGUUCCCCAGGCAGCUCCGGAAGAGCGGGCGGCGCGAGCUCCUCAUCCUCACCAUCGCCGUCAUGUGCUACCUGAUAGGGCUUUUCCUGGUCACCGAGGGCGGGAUGUACAUCUUCCAGCUGUUUGACUACUAUGCUUCCAGUGGCAUAUGCCUGCUGUUCCUGUCAUUGUUUGAAGUGGUCUGCAUAAGCUGGGUGUAUGGGGCGGACCGUUUCUAUGACAACAUUGAGGACAUGAUUGGCUACCGGCCAUGGCCCCUGGUGAAGAUCUCCUGGCUCUUCCUGACCCCUGGACUUUGCCUGGCCACUUUCCUCUUCUCCUUGAGCAAGUACACCCCCCUCAAGUACAACAACGUCUAUGUGUACCCGCCCUGGGGAUACUCCAUUGGCUGGUUCCUGGCUCUGUCCUCCAUGGUCUGUGUCCCACUCUUCGUCGUCAUCACCCUCCUGAAGACUCGGGGUCCUUUCAGGAAGGUUUACUUCUGAAACCAGCGAGACCACUGAACCAUCGGGAGGAAAAAAAAACUCCAGACGCGCCGCCUUCAGAGUUGUAGCACUCAUCGCGAAGGUCCGCAGUUUCACUCCGGAGCUGGUGAGACCACGAACCUACCAGAAGGAAAAAACUCCGAACACAUCUGAACGUUAGAAGGAACAAACUCCGGACACGCCGCCUUUAAGAACUGUAACCCUCACUGUGAGGGUCUGCGGCUUCAUGCUUGAAGUCAGUGAGACCAAGAACCCACUUACUCUGGGCACACUUUCAUCUCGUUUCCUUUGGUGUUUGAGUUGCAGACUGGUGAACAGAGGCCAAAUCUGGCAGCUACAAUUUGGCCAGUGUGGCAUGAAAAAAUUGAUUUUUGCAGCAGAAGCCCUGAGGCAUGCUGGAGUUUGCCACAGUCUUCCCACUUCUGUCACACCUGGUUUUCUCACAUAUUCGCUUUUGCGUUUGAAUUCAUAAUCUGUGCCCUAGCGGAGAAAGUGAGAACUUUGGGCAGGGGAGGGAACAGGAGCCCUUGGGUGCGACGCAAGGGACAGCAGAGGGCAGUGGUUGGGGGUCCUGGUGCCUCAGAAGGGGUGGUGGUAGCAGGGUUACCACAGGCUCCAGCCUGCUCCGGUGUGGACCUCACACCCUAUGAUGCUAUUCAUCCAUGAAUCCUGGGUCAAGUCUCUCUCCCACCUGGACAUUCUCCCGAAGAAGGGUAGUGGAUACCUCUAAUUUCAGAGCUACAUCUCAAUAGAUGUGUUAACAUCAGCAGCGCCCACGUGGCAGAGUACACCAAAGCUUAAUUGUCUGGGGGGACAGUUGGCCCAAUAGAGAGGCCCACGUGGAAUCCAGGCCUCCCACUAAUGGUCAACAGCAGCAGCUUGCUGCAAGGUGAAUACACUGCGUGGAAAUGUAUCCUCCCAGCUGGCCAAGGCUUCUAGUGGCAGCAGCCCUGGCUGACACAGGGACUACAGCCUUACAGAGGCACUGAGCCAGAAAUGCCCAGCCAAGUGGGCCCCAAAUGCCUGACCCCAGUGAGAGGUGAGAAAUGCAUAUGGUUGUUUUAAGCCGUAAGCUUUGGGGUGAUUUUUUACACAGCAGUAGAUAAUACCUAUCCUUGGAUCCAAUUGCUUGCAGUUCCUUCACCUGGCUGACAGCUGCUGUGGCUGCCGGUGGAAGGCCUCGGCUCCUCUCAUGUGGGCUCUCUGUUGGGUCAAGUGUGCUCCUGGACAGCUGAGCUUUAGCGUGCACUGUGGCCUGUGGGUGCUGUCGUGGCCACUUCCCAGAGCGCGAGAGUCACCCUCUUUGAGAGUCAGGCGUGGCCCCUCUUCAGAGGCGUCCCUCAGCCCCCUCGUGCCCUUCUGCCUGAGCCUCCUGCCUCUCUGCCACAGCCUCACCUCCUCUGACCCCUCCAGAGCCCUCCCCUGACCCUGGGCUCACCCUGUCCUUGCUGUGAGGAGGUGAAGACUGGCUGUGUCUGUCCCUGCCACCUCCGUGCUCGCAUGCCCAGCUUCCUUGCAGGUUCUGCUGCUCAGUGAAGUAACAAGGGCUGAUUGGAUCUAACAGGGAUGAGAAGCUUGUUAACCACCCAUUGAUGCAGCGGCCAUGGGAGGAUGUGUUUGCCAGACAGGAUGGGGUGAGAUGAGAGCCAAGCCUGGCAGGUGGCACAGGGUUGAGGUGGGUCAGUGCCCUGGGCCCUGGCGACCCGCACUCCAGCGCUCUCUGCUUCCAGUCUGGCCACAGCAGGGGCAGAUGGCCUGUCAGGUCUGAGGAACCUGCUGGCACGUGACUGGGAAGUAACGGGAGGCGAGUGCAAGUUGCCAGAUGAUGCCACAGACAGAGAGGGGAGCUUGCUCCCUGCCAAGGCUGAGUCCUUGCAGGCUCGUGUCCAUCCACAGGGUCAGUGCAUAACCUGUGGCUAUAACAAGAGUCUAGCCGGAACUUCUGGUGCAGUCACAUUCUGAGGCUUUUUCUGCCCAAGCACAUCUCACUAACACACAGAGGGUGGCUGUCACAUCCAAAAGGCCCUGGCCCCGAGGCCAGAACUCUGACACUGCACCCCAGCAUGAGGGACUCGAAGUGGGCAAGUCCCUUCCCCAAGCAGGACUCAGUCCCCAUCUCACUAAGACACGGGCACAGGGAGCAAGCAAAGGUAGCCAGAGUGGGUCCUGAACAAGUGCAUUUGGAAUUUGGGUUUGUCAUGGAGAGGAGGUUCCGGGGAGCAGGACAGAGGGUAGCCAUGACAGCGGGUGGGGCCGGGGGAGCGGCCUUACCCGGCCAGCUGUCCGGAGACCUGGGCUCACUGUCCAGCCUCAGCCUUUUCCUCUGGGUUAAUUAAAGUUGUUGUUUUCCUCUUGGUUCUUUAGGGUGUUUUACAUAGACACUCAGACUGUCUGGAAAUAAUGACAGUUUUAUGUCUCCGAUCAUGAUUCUUUCUCUUAUCUUCCUUCACUUGGUAACUAGAAGUGGUGGCAGCUGGCAUCCUUGCUUCCUUCCUGGUUUUGACAGGAACCCUAACAUUUCAUUAGGAAGUAUGACGGCUGAUGAUUUUUUUUUUUUUUUGAGACAGUUUCAUUCUGUCCCCCAGGCUGGAGCGCAGUGGCUUGAUCUCAGCUCACUACAACCUCUGCCUCCUGGGUUCAAGUGAUUCUCCUGCCUCAUCCUCCCCAGUAGCUGGAUUACAGGCAUAAGCCACCAUGCUUGGCUAAUUUUUGUAUUUUUAUUUUUUUAUUUAUUUAUUUUUGAGACGGAGUCUUGCUCUGUCGCCCAGGCUAGAGUGCAGUGGCGCCAUCUCAGCUCAUUGCAAGCUCCGCCUCCCGGGUUCACGCCAUUCUCCUGCCUCAGCCUCCCGAGUAGCUGGGACUACAGGCGCCCGCCACCACGCCCGGCUAAUUUUUUGUAUUUUUAGUAGAGAUGGGGUUUCACCGUGUUAGCCAGGAUGGUCUCGAUCUCCUGACCUCGUGAUCCGCCCGCCUCGGCCUCCCAAAGUGCUGGGAUUACAGGCAUGAACCACCGAAUUUUUGUGUUUUUAGUAGAGAUGAGGUUUUGCCAUGUUGGCCAGACUGGUCUCGAACUCCUGAUCUCAAGUGAUCCACCCACCUCGGCCUCCCAAAGUGCUGGGAUUACAGGUGUGAGCCACCAUGCCUGGCCAGCUGAUGAUUUUUGAUAGAUAUCAUUUACUGGGCUAUGAAGUUUUCUUCCAUUCCAAGUUCUAUAGGUUUUUUUCAAAUCAACAGUAAGGGUUGAAUUUUAUGGAUUGCUUUUUCUGCAUCUAUUGAGAUAAUUAUAUUGUUUUUCUCCUUUAAUUUGUUAAUGUAACAAAUUAUUAUAUUUUUCUAAUAUUCAAUCAUCUGUUCAUUCUUGGGGCAAACCCUACUUGGUUAUGGCAUAUUUUUUUUUGUUAUUCAGUACUAGGUUCAGUUUGCUAAUAUUGUGUUUAGAAUUUCUGAAUUUAUGCCCAUAAACAAGAUUGGUUGGUAGUCUUCUUUUUCUCAUACCGUGCUUGUCUGCUUUAGUUUUUGUUUUUGAGAUUACACCAGGCUCAUGAAAAGGAGUUUGGAGAUGUUCUGUUUCUCUUUUCUGAAAGAGUUAAUAUGAUAUUGGAAUUAUCUGUUCCUUGAAGUGUAGUAGAAUUUUGUAAAAUCA